UCUGAAUGAGGUGGGCUGUCACAGUGAGAACUUUUGAAGAUAUGUCUAUCUGGACUCAUGCUGAAAAUUCAGAAGUAUUUUUUCCAUGUCAUCAUUAUAAGUAGAAACUGAGGCUGAAACACUGCUCACAUUCUGAUUAUUGUGAAGGUGAAAUUCUAUCCAUGACGCCUGCAGGCUCUCCUCCUGCAGCUCAGACGUCACUCUCUGAUGUGACACUAGAGUGCUGCUGUGGCAAAUGGGGUUCACAUAAAAUGUAAGCUGUGCUCUGGGCUGUGCCUCAGUGGCAGAUGGUAGCGGUAAAGAGAGGACACUAGCAACUAGGAGAAAGUAAACAGGAGUGCUGUAGCCCAGUGCCAGGGAGUACAGAGCCACUGCUCUAAAAUGUAAAUAGCCAAAAAGAACACUAUUCAGCCAUUUUUGUAGCAGAGUGAAAGCCUAGCUUCAGCAGACACCUGGCUUCAAGCUGCUAAACCAACUCCUGUUAUGAAGAUGUGAAAAGUUUAUUUGUCAUUGAAUAUAAGCAAUUAGUAUACACAGAUGGCCUCUUCAGUAUCCAGGUGAAUUUAGGAUGAACUAUAUAUGACAUGGUGCUGAAAAUUCUUCUACUUGUGGACUAAUUAUGAUGACCAUCUUUCUGACUUUGCAGUCUCUUAAGCAGAUUGAUGAUGAUGUAUGUCACAUUCAAGUUUAAUUGUGUAAUAAGACCAUUUUCUUUCUGUUCUAUUAUUGUGGAGUUUCUCUGAAAAUAGAGAAAAUUUUUCUUUUAAUUAUUGUUUCCACAGAGUGUCUAGAAUUACCAGACAUGAUAUAAACACAUAAGGUGCCAACCAGAAUUUACUGUAGAGGGGACUUUCCCUCUCAGACUUUGAGUCAGCCCAUACUUGCGCAGCAAAAUGCAUGCUGUCCAUUAAAUAUGCACGUGGAAUUUUGUCUCUGCCUAUUUGGUAUUGAUAGUUCCUCUACUGUCACUUCUAGAGAGGCUAGACCCAAUUUCUACAAACUUCACAGGGCAGCAAUUAAUUAAUCAUUUAACCUUUUUCAGUGACUCUUGUAUCUUCAGAUUUGAAACUGAUUCAGAAACUAUGGAGCCCAGAAACCCAAUCAGAGUAACAUGUGUGUGCUGAGUAGACAUAGAGACAUGAGAAUCUCCACUUUCCCCUUCCUCCUCUUGCUAAAUGCUCACAAAUGUACAGGUAAACACCUGUGGCUACUCCAGUCGUUCAGGCCCUAAACUUGAAGCUCCAAAUUUUGAAUCCAGGUCUUGAGAUUUGGGGGAAAAAAAAACUUACCUAAGAAAUGCAAGUCCCUUUGGUUAUCAAACUCAGACAUUAAAAUGAAAGUACUGUUAUGUCUUUCUCCCCCCUUUGAACUAUGUAUUCAUCUCUUGAAACUGUUCACUAUUGCCACAAGUAAUUAUAAAUUAAACUAAUAAUGCCACAUUAGACACUAUAUCCCAUACCCUAAACCAUAAUAAUAUAUAUGUAAUCAAUAAUCGAUGUUAUUUCUGUAAAUAAAUAAAAAUUUCUGACAAUCAACUUUGUAUCAGCCCACUCUCUGUCCCUGUCUUGUUGUCUUUACAAAUUGUCUUGUAACUGCUGGUAAUCAAAAUGCAGAUUCCAGGCAACUUGAAUCUUUGCUCCCAGGUUAUAAUCCUUAAGCUUGACCCAAGUAAACUAUCUACUUAUAUUCAUGUUCUUUCAGCUUUUUUUUUUUUUUUUCAUGUAGACUUACCAUUUAGAAUGUGCUAGAGUAGUCUCUAUGAGGGGAUCUCUCCUUUGAUUGUAUUCCACUUGCUGUAACACCAAAGGAUGCAGAGCCAGGUGGAUCCUACCUGGAAUCUGCAGAUAAGGUCUGGCCUCUGCCUGGGAUUUACAAGAAAGGACCAGAACUUGGAUUGAGAAUGUACAGAAAAUGAACAAAAGUCAUUUUCUGCAUUGUGAAUGUAAACAUAGACAUCUUACAGCCCCCAUUUGGGAGUGUGGCUCUUUGAGAUUUUCACAUCUUGUUCAUUGACCUGCUACAGUUAUGUGAGGGGCUCCAGGAGAAAUAGACUCAGAUGGCAGAAUCUGUAAGUGUAAAUAAGCAUCUUAGGAGUGAGAGAUCGGGGCCACAAAGUAUCCAGAGCCAUGACCACAAUUAUAUUUAGCUGUAAAAUGUAAUACUAGAGUAGAGUAUUUUUGAUCUUUCUCUUACCCAAGAGCUAGCAAAUCAGAAUGGGUGAUCCAGGUUCUGGAGCUCCACCAGGGCAGUUCCAUUUUCUAUUCAGAGUUAGCCUGAGUCUCUCCAGCCUGGCUUAUCAUUGGGCCAUGAGGCCUGGGUCACUGGGAAUCUCUCACAAUCACCCAGGUGUCUUUGAGGCAUUUGAGGAUGUCCAGAGCAGAAUUUUGUCAGGCUGACAAGAGUGGUUAAUUCUGCUUCUGUCUCAGUGUAAGAGAAAUGAGUCAUCCUGUGUUUGUUCAUUCCCUCAUACAAGAGAUAUCUUUGGUUGGUACCCCGAUGACAGCUUCUCCAGUUUCCUGGUACUUGGAUAAUAAGGAGAAGAUCUGGAGACCCAGAUAGAUAAACUAGCUCCUUCCACUUCAUAUGGGCAUUAAAAAAAUACAUGAAGCAGUCAUAGUUCCUACAAUCCAGAAACUUUUAGUCUAGACUAGCUACUGGAUAAGUAAUUGAAGUGUGCAUCAUAUGGUUGGUAUAAUAAAUAGAUGUGUUAAAAAUCUUGGGCUUUAGACCACUUUCUUUAUAUUGUUGUGACUUCUGAUGUCUACACCUGAAGGGAGAUUUAUGAACAAAAUAAUUGUUAUAAAUUCUUUUUUUUUUUUGAGAUGGUGUUUCACUCUGUCACCUGGUCUGGCUUGCAGUGGCACGAUCUCGGCUCACUGUAAACUCUGCCGCCCGGGUUCAGGUGACUUUCCCUUCUCAGCCUCCCGAGUAGCUGGGAUUACAGUUGCCUGCCACUGCACCUAGCUAAUUUUUGUAUUUUUACUAGAGGCGGGGUUUCAUCAUCUGGAUCAGGCUGGUCUUUAACUGCUUGACCUCGUUCUGCACCCGCCUUGGUCUCCCAAAGUCUUGAGAUUACAAGCAUGACCCACCGCGCUUGGCCGUAUAUUUUCUAUUUCUUUUACCUUGCUAACUGUAGAUAUUUAUUUUCUAAUAAAAUUACCCUAGAAAACCUUAAGGGAUUUGUUUAAGUUGCAUACUAGUAUAUAGUAUAAAGUUGUCAGGGCAGUGACUAGAAAAGAUAAAAACUACAGAAACUCUGGGAUUUAAGUUUCUUUUAGGUAAGCUUAGAAACAAAACAAAACUGGAAGUUUCCUAGUUGCAUAGAGAACAGAAUUCUACAUAGGGUUCUCACCCUGCCCCAGACGUGUUCAGAUUCAUCCUUUUUGGAGACCUUAGUUAGGUCUGAACCUACCCUGGAGUAUUGCCUCACAGAACUCAUUAAAGGAGAUCAGAGUUUUGGCUGCUGAAUCCUGCUGCCUUUCUAGAGCUGGUGCUCACAAUUUCCUGAAAUUCAAAAGCAGAUAAAUCGGGAAAAAAAGUAUGUUUUGUAAGGUGUUUGUUUUUAAAUUUUUUAUUAAAACCAGUGCUUGCAGAGACAUUGUAUUUAGCAACUUGUUUUCUAUUCCUGCAGAUCCAGUAGUUGCUGCACAAGUCAAAAAAGUAAAUAUAAACAGAAUGAAAUUUUCUCUAGACUACAUUAAACUCUUCUGUAUCUCUUUCAUCUGUCUAUAUUUAGCUUUUAUUCUAUACAAUUUUUUAAAAAAUUUGAUGACAGAGAAACAGAAGAAAAAAUAAAAAUGGGCCCUUUAUCUAAAUCCUGAAAAUUAAGAAACACUUAGUACCAGCUCCCCGGGUGUUAAGAGAAUUAAAUCAUAUAAUGUGUUAUGCCCAGCACCGUGCUCUGUAUCAUACUCUAGCACAUAGUGCCUGCUUAAUAAACAUUGCAUUAGUACCUGUGUACAUGUUCUUUUUAAAAUACAGACUUAUUCAGAUAUUGCUGUCUUCUGUUUCCUCUGUAAAUUUUAAAGAGCCAGCAAAAAAUAUAAAACUUUUAAAUGGAAUGGGCUGUCCUUAUUUUUACUAGAAGUAUUUGGUUAUGGCAAGAGUGUUAAGUGUAAGGGACCCUGUGCUGUUCCUGCUUUCUCUAACUAAUGCUCAUAAUGAGCCAGUGGGGAGCAACAUCAGCAUUGACAGGGGACUUGUUUAAAACACUCAUUCAUAAACCCUCUUCAAACAUACAGAAUCACAUUACAGAAUGUGCGGCCACAAUUAUCAAGUGAUUUAUAAGCUCGUUAAAGCUUGAGAGGCAAUGCUUAGCUUAGUGGUUAUCAGCCCAGGCUUCUCAUUAGGAUCACAUGACCAAUUUGCUGAAAUCUCUUGUACCCUCCCCACAGCUUCUGUUUAUUGUUGUGGGUGGAAGCAUCCAUGUUUUUUUAAUGAAGUGCCUCAUGUGACUCUAAGGUGAUUCCAGAAUCAAGUAUAAGGGCUUUAAAAUAUAUUCAUGAGAGUUAAAUUCCACCUGUGAACUAGAGGGUGGUCACAGGGCCUAUUCUAUUUGGGUUUGGUAGGGACAGGUAAGUGUGGUGCAUAUUUCCAUUACUGUAGCAAAAGUUGCUGGUGUCUAUGGCAGGGGAGGGCACCUGAGGACAGGAAAGGAGAAACUUAUAUUUUUAUCUUCAUGGAGCAGUUCAUUGUUCCCGAAUCUCUUCUGUUUUAAAGGACAGAAAUGGGUGGCUUUUUCUGUCUUUUUCUGCCAGAAGAUGUCAUGCUAGCAGGUAAACAUGUGGUACACCUUUAAAGGCAUAUUCUCCAGAUGCAGGUGUAAUUUGUACAGAGAAUCUCAUCUGAGAAGAAACUCCAGGGAAGGAGGAGAAAGAAAAAAAAAUGGCUUUUCUUCAGGUAAACAUGUGUCAGAUGAAGAGCUGUGUCCACUCUGCCUCCUGGACUGCCAUGCGUUUAGUACUCACAAACCUUUACUUCUCUACUUUUGUUUUUCCUCCGUGAGUUUGAUUUAACUACUUCUUAAAAUUCCUAUGAUGGUCAAGGAUCUUUGAAAAAUAUUUCUUUUUUAUAUCCCACAGACUUCUCUACAUUCUGUUUGUCAUAGCUUCUUAUAUGCCAUGCAGAAUUAUCAGCAAGAAUUUAUGAUCCACAUUAUUAAAAAUAUUCCCUUUGUGGCUGUUGAACACAGAAAGAUGUGGGUACUCAAGAUUCCUAUUGGGGAAAACUGUGGUCCUUAGUAAAGAUGGUAAAGUAAAAGCCUCCACUCGUGUUCCAUUAGCUAUAUGCAGAAGAUAAUUCAGAAAAUGCUUAUUUAAAUGGGAUAGAAUUUAUUACCCAGAAUGUUCUGAAAAAAAUUAUUAGGAGAUACUUGCUCUCUAGGGUGCUAAAUGAAGCCUAUUUAAAAUUACUACUAAAAAUUACAGAACAUAGGAGUUAACUGUAUUUUGGAGUUUGCAUAAAACUGAUGUUUCUUUAUGGUUAAAUUCAGAUUAUAAUUUACGUUAUUUGGGAGGAAUAUUUCAACAGUGAUACUGUGUUCUGUGUGCAUUAACACAUCAGAAAAAUUUGUCCUAGUGCAGUUAAUGGUUAAUGAUUCACUUGGUGAAGUAGCUCUCUCUCACAGAUUUUUUCACUAUAGUUAAUUAUUUUUCUCUUCAUUAUUAAGCAUCCUUAUCCAGCGGAUUUGCAUAAACCAUCACAUUUAAUCUGUCAGUUGUCCUUUUUUCUUUUUUUUUCUAUAUAGUUUUCUAUGGAAGAUGAAGGCUGUUAUCUUUGUUUACAGGCCACAAAAACUUGGAAAAACACAGGCUCUUCCACUUACUGGAUGUUUGACAAAAUAUCCUUCUCGGGCCAAAAACAUUGACAUUUUUGGGACCAUUGCAAUUUAGAGAUGUGGCCAUAGAAUUCUCUCUGGAGGAGUGGCAUUGCCUGGACACUGCACAGCGGAAUCUAUAUAGGAAUGUGAUGUUAGAGAACUACAGUAACCUGGUCUUCCUUGGUAUUGUUGUCUCUAAGCCAGACCUGAUCGCCCAUCUGGAGCAAGGAAAAAAACCUUUGACUAUGAAGAGACAUGAGAUGGUAGCCAACCCCUCAGUUAUAUGUUCUCAUUUUGCCCAAGAUCUUUGGCCAGAGCAGAACAUAAAAGAUUCUUUCCAAAAAGUGAUACUGAGAAGAUAUGAAAAACGUGGACAUGGAAAUUUACAGUUAAUAAAAAGGUGUGAAAGUGUAGAUGAGUGUAAGGUGCACACAGGAGGUUAUAAUGGACUUAACCAGUGUAGUACAACUACCCAGAGCAAAGUAUUUCAAUGUGAUAAAUAUGGGAAAGUCUUUCAUAAAUUUUCAAAUUCAAAUAGACAUAAUAUAAGACAUACUGAAAAAAAACCUUUCAAAUGCAUAGAAUGUGGCAAAGCUUUUAACCAGUUCUCAACCCUUAUAACACAUAAGAAAAUUCAUACUGGAGAGAAACCCUACAUUUGUGAAGAAUGUGGCAAAGCCUUUAAGUACUCCUCUGCCCUUAAUACACAUAAGAGAAUUCAUACUGGAGAGAAACCAUACAAGUGUGAUAAAUGUGACAAAGCCUUUAUUGCAUCCUCAACCCUUAGUAAACAUGAGAUCAUUCAUACUGGAAAGAAACCCUACAAGUGUGAAGAAUGUGGCAAAGCUUUUAACCAAUCCUCGACACUUACUAAACAUAAGAAAAUUCAUACUGGAGAGAAACCCUACAAAUGUGAAGAAUGUGGCAAAGCUUUUAACCAAUCCUCAACACUUACUAAACAUAAGAAAAUUCAUACUGGAGAGAAGCCCUACGUUUGUGAAGAAUGUGGCAAAGCCUUUAAGUACUCCCGUAUCCUUACUACACAUAAGAGAAUUCAUACUGGAGAGAAACCAUACAAGUGUAAUAAAUGUGGCAAAGCCUUUAUUGCAUCCUCAACCCUUAGUAGACAUGAGUUCAUUCAUAUGGGAAAGAAACAUUACAAAUGUGAAGAAUGUGGCAAAGCCUUCAUUUGGUCCUCAGUCCUAACUAGACAUAAGAGAGUUCAUACUGGAGAGAAGCCCUACAAAUGUGAAGAAUGUGGCAAAGCCUUUAAGUACUCCUCUACCCUUAGUUCACAUAAGAGAAGUCAUACUGGAGAGAAACCCUACAAAUGUGAAGAAUGUGGCAAAGCCUUUGUUGCAUCCUCAACCCUUAGUAAACAUGAGAUCAUUCAUACUGGAAAGAAACCCUACAAGUGUGAAGAAUGUGGCAAAGCUUUUAACCAGUCCUCAUCCCUUACUAAACAUAAGAAAAUUCAUACUGGAGAGAAACCCUACAAAUGUGAAGAAUGUGGCAAAGCUUUUAACCAGUCCUCUUCCCUUACUAAACAUAAGAAAAUUCAUACUGGAGAGAAACCCUACAAAUGUGAAGAAUGUGGCAAAGCUUUUAACCAGUCCUCAACCCUUAUUAAACAUAAGAAAAUUCAUACUAGAGAGAAACCCUACAAAUGUGAAGAAUGUGGCAAAGCUUUUCACCUAUCCACACACCUUACUACACAUAAGAUACUUCAUACUGGAGAGAAACCUUAUAGAUGUAGAGAAUGUGGCAAAGCUUUUAACCAUUCUGCAACCCUUUCUUCACAUAAGAAAAUCCAUUCUGGAGAGAAACCAUACGAGUGUGAUAAAUGUGGCAAAGCCUUUAUUUCACCCUCAAGCCUUAGUAGACAUGAGAUAAUUCAUACUGGGGAGAAACCCUAGAAGUGUGAAGAAUGUGGCAAAGCCUUCAAGUGGUCCUCACACCUUACUAUACACUGAGAGUUCUGAACUUACUCUGUAACCAUCCCAAACUCCUCCCAGGCACAGUCUGGCAGAGGUCCUGCCAUUUCGGAGACCUGGAGGAAGUGGCCCAUUUACAGCCAUGUAGGCAGGCCUGCAGACCUUGGCCUUUACUACGGUACCUGAAGUGGUUCAAUGACUCAGUUUCAGUUACCUGAGCCACAGCUUAAGGUCAGUUCUGCCUAUAUAGAAACCCACACAGUUAACCUGAGGAAAUGCUCUCUGGUACUCACUGAAAGCCACACUCAUCCACAUCCUGAUACAAGGCCCACCAUAUGCAGACCUGACUGCCAAAACAUGCCCUAGUGUCUGCCGUACAGAGUGAAGUCCUGAAGGAUAUUUAGUCUGUCCAAAACUAAAAUGAAGAUUUCAACUCCCCAACCCCCUCUAACAAGCCAGCUAAAGGUGGACUAUAGUGCAGACCCAGCAACCUUGUGACCAGGCUAAAACCCCUCAUCACUACAAAUUCAGAGGGCAUCUCAUCACCCUAAGGGCCCAACGAAAGAUCUUUACCUUCUAACAUCAGUUUAUGAAAACUUGAAAAGGUGUUUGCUCCAUCAAAUUCAGACACCAGUACAAAACUAUAUUAUGCCCAUUGUCUGGUUCUAUUUUAAUGUAGCACUGGAAGUGUGUGGCAGAAGAAUUAGUCAAAGAAAUAAAAAUAGCCAUUGAAAUUGAA